GUGACUAGGAAGGAGCUAGUGGACUAGAGCCAGGGUAAGGGGAUCUGCUAGAAGUUGGUCUUCCGCCAGGACUAGAGUUUCCUCGCGGUAACAGCCUCCGUGGCCUCCGGAGGACCAUGUCAUUAGACUUUGGCAGUGUGGCACUACCAGUGCAAAAUGAAGAUGAAGAGUAUGACGAAGAGGACUAUGAAAGAGAGAAAGAGUUGCAGCAGUUACUCACAGACCUUCCCCAUGACAUGCUGGAUGACGACCUCUCCUCUCCAGAGCUCCAGUAUUCGGACUGCAGCGAGGAUGGCACAGACGGACAACCACAUCAUCCUGAGCAAUUGGAGAUGAGCUGGAAUGAGCAAAUGCUGCCCAAAUCUCAAAGUGUAAAUGGCUAUAAUGAAAUUCAGAGUUUAUAUGCUGGAGAAAAAUGUGGUAAUGUCUGGGAAGAAAAUAGAAGUAAAACUGAAGACCGACAUCCUGUGUACCAUCCUGAAGAAGGUGGAGAUGAAGGUGGAAGUGGUUAUAGUCCUCCAAGUAAAUGUGAACAGACUGAUUUAUAUCACCUUCCUGAAAACUUUAGGCCAUAUACCAAUGGUCAGAAGCAGGAAUUUAAUAACCAAGCAACCAAUGUAAUUAAAUUUUCAGAUCCUCAAUGGAACCAUUUUCAGGGUCCCAGUUGUCAAGGUUUGGAACCGUAUAAUAAAGUGACAUAUAAACCUUAUCAGUCUUCUGCCCAGAAUAAUGGCUCACCAGCCCAGGAGAUAACAGGAAGUGACACAUUCGAAGGCCUGCAACAACAAUUUUUAGGAGCUAAUGAGAACUCUGCAGAAAAUAUGCAGAUUAUUCAACUUCAGGUUCUUAACAAAGCAAAAGAGAGACAACUGGAGAACUUAAUUGAAAAGUUAAAUGAAAGUGAACGUCAAAUUCGAUAUCUGAAUCACCAGCUUGUAAUAAUAAAAGAUGAAAAGGAUGGUUUGACUCUCAGCCUUCGAGAAUCACAGAAACUCUUUCAGAAUGGAAAAGAAAGAGAGAUACAGCUUGAAGCUCAAAUAAAAGCACUGGAGACUCAGAUACAAGCAUUAAAAGUCAAUGAAGAACAGAUGAUCAAGAAGUCCAGAACAACUGAAAUGGCUCUGGAAAGCUUGAAGCAGCAGCUGGUGGACCUUCAUCAUUCUGAAUCACUUCAACGAGCUAGAGAACAGCAUGAGAGCAUUGUUAUGGGCCUCACAAAGAAGUACGAAGAGCAAGUAUUGUCCUUACAAAAGAAUUUGGAUGCCACAGUCACCGCACUUAAAGAACAGGAAGACAUUUGCUCUCGUCUGAAAGAUCACGUGAAACAACUGGAAAGGAAUCAAGAAGCAAUCAAGUUAGAAAAGACUGAGAUCAUUAAUAAGUUGACAAGAAGUCUAGAGGAGAGUCAAAAGCAGUGUGCCCACUUGUUGCAGUCCGGGUCAGUACAAGAGGUGGCUCAGCUACAGUUCCAGCUGCAGCAAGCACAGAAGGCACAUGCUAUGAGUGCAAACAUGAACAAGGCUUUGCAAGAAGAAUUAACAGAACUAAAAGAUGAAAUUUCUCUCUAUGAAUCUGCUGCAAAACUAGGAAUACAUCCAAGUGACUCAGAAGGAGAAUUAAAUAUAGAACUCACUGAAUCGUAUGUGGAUUUGGGUAUUAAAAAGGUCAACUGGAAAAAAUCCAAAGUUACCAGCAUUGUACAAGAAGAAGACCCAAAUGAAGAGCUUUCAAAAGAUGAGUUCAUUCUGAAGUUAAAGGCAGAAGUACAGCGUUUGCUGGGUAGCAACUCAAUGAAGCGUCAUCUGGUGUCUCAGUUACAAAAUGACCUCAAAGACUGUCAUAAGAAAAUUGAAGAUCUCCACCAAGUGAAGAAGGAUGAAAAAAGCAUUGAGGUUGAGACUAAAACAGAUACCUCAGAAAAACCAAAGAAUCAAUUAUGGCCUGAGUCUUCUACUUCUGAUGUUGUCAGAGAUGAUAUUCUGCUGCUUAAAAAUGAAAUUCAAGUUUUACAACAACAAAAUCAGGAACUUAAAGAAACUGAAGGAAAACUGAGAAAUACAAAUCAAGACUUAUGUAAUCAAAUGAGACAAAUGGUACAAGAUUUUGACCAUGACAAACAAGAAGCUGUGGAUAGGUGUGAAAGGACUUAUCAGCAGCACCAUGAAGCCAUGAAAACUCAAAUACGUGAAAGCCUAUUAGCAAAGCAUGCUUUGGAGAAGCAGCAGCUCUUUGAGGCUUAUGAGAGAACUCAUUUGCAACUGAGGUCUGAGUUGGAUAAGUUGAAUAAGGAGGUGACUGCUGUGCAGGAAUGUUACCUAGAAGUGUGCAGAGAGAAGGAUAAUCUAGAAUUGACUCUCAGGAAGACCACUGAAAAGGAGCAACAGACUCAGGAGAAGAUCAAAGAAAAACUCAUUCAACAGCUUGAAAAGGAGUGGCAGUCUAAGCUGGAUCAAACUAUAAAGGCAAUGAAAAAGAAGACCUUAGAUUGUGGCAGCCAAACUGACCAAGUAACCACCAGUGAUGUUAUUUCCAAGAAAGAGAUGGCAAUUAUGAUAGAAGAGCAGAAGUGCACAAUCCAGCAAAACUUAGAACAAGAGAAGGACAUAGCCAUCAAGGGGGCUAUGAAGAAACUCGAAAUUGAAUUGGAACUCAAACAUUGUGAAAAUAUUACCAAACAGGUAGAAAUAGCUGUGCAAAAUGCUCAUCAGCGAUGGCUGGGAGAACUACCAGAGCUGGCAGAGUAUCAAGCACUUGUGAAGGCAGAACAGAAAAAGUGGGAAGAACAGCAUGAGGUCUCUGUGAACAAAAGGAUAUCAUUUGCUGUUUCUGAAGCUAAAGAGAAAUGGAAGAGUGAGCUUGAAAAUAUGAGGAAAAAUAUACUUCCUGGAAAGGAAUUGGAAGAGAAGAUUCAUUCUCUUCAGAAGGAACUUGAGUUAAAGAACGAAGAAGUCCCUGUGGUCAUCAGGGCUGAGUUAGCUAAGGCUCGGAGUGAAUGGAACAAAGAAAAGCAAGAAGAAAUCCACAGAAUCCAAGAACAAAAUGAGCAAGAUUACCGGCAAUUUUUAGAUGAUCACCGAAAUAAAAUUAAUGAGGUGCUUGCGGCAGCUAAAGAAGACUUUAUGAAACAAAAAACUGAACUACUUCUUCAGAAGGAGACAGAAUUACAAACUUGUCUAGACCAGAGUCGUAGAGAAUGGACUAUGCAGGAAGCCAAGCGGAUCCAACUGGAAAUCUAUCAGUAUGAGGAAGACAUCCUGACUGUACUUGGGGUUCUUUUAAGUGAUACCCAAAAGGAGCACAUCAGUGAUUCUGAGGACAAGCAGCUUUUGGAAAUCAUGUCGACUUGUUCUUCAAAAUGGAUGUCUGUGCAAUAUUUUGAAAAACUAAAGGGCUGCAUACAGAAAGCAUUUCAAGAUACACUUCCUCUGCUUGUAGAAAACGCUGACCCAGAAUGGAAAAAGAGAAAUAUGGCCGAGCUCUCUAAGGAUUCUGCCAGCCAGGGCACUGGCCAAGGAGACCCUGGACCUGCUGCUGGACACCAUGCUCAGCCCUUGGCCUUACAAGCAACAGAAGCAGAAGCUGAUAAGAAAAAGGUCCUUGAAAUUAAGGAUUUAUGCUGUGGACACUGCUUCCAAGAACUUGAAAAGGCAAAGCAGGAAUGUCAAGAUCUGAAAGGAAAACUGGAGAAAUGCUGUAGGCAUCUUCAGCAUUUAGAAAGGAAGCACAAAGCUGUAGUGGAAAAAAUUGGAGAAGAGAAUAAUAAAGUUGUUGAAGAAUUAAUAGAAGAAAACAACGACAUGAAGAAUAAAUUGGAAGAAUUGCAAACACUUUGUAAAACACCACCAAGGUCAUUGUCAGCAGGGGCCAUUGAAAAUGCUUGCCUGCCAUGCAGUGGGGGAGCCUUGGAAGAACUUCGUGGGCAGUACAUUAAAGCUGUAAAAAAAAUUAAAUGUGACAUGCUUCGUUAUAUUCAGGAGAGUAAGGAACGAGCUGCAGAAAUGGUAAAAGCAGAGGUACUGCGAGAACGUCAAGAAACCGCCCGAAAGAUGCGCAAAUAUUAUUUGAUUUGCCUCCAACAGAUUUUGCAGGAUGAUGGAAAAGAAGGGGCUGAGAAAAAGAUUAUGAAUGCUGCUAGCAAACUUGCUACAAUGGCAAAAUUACUGGAAACACCUAUUUCUAAGCCAGAUAACUUAGGUGGUGAUGGGGAGACGGCAAGAUGCAUCCUCCUCCUCCUGAUAACCAUCUCUAAAAGCAAGAACCGAGAAGGAAAACUUUUUGGGCUUGGAAAGCUCUGUCACCUUAACUCUUGACCAGGGAUAAAUAAGUCUAAAAAUUGGUCCUGGACUUCAGUGCUUGAAUUCACAUACAGCUAUAGUAAGGAACAAACCAUCUUGUCAAAGUCUCACUUGUAUUCCUGAAGAUACAAUGCUCCUUCUCCAACAGUUAGGCUGUCAUCUCUCACUCUAGAAAAAAACUCUAAAACAGCCAAGUUUAUGCUCCCUAUGGAUCUGGUUGGUGCUUGAUCGUUUUAAGCCCUUGUUUUUAGUAAACUUAGAAUCUAGGCUCGUUGCUCACCUACCUUUUCCACUUGGUUCAAAAUCCAUGUCAGUUAUUUAAACUCUCAACAUUAAGGUUGAAAUUGGAAGUUCUCUUGCUUUCUGCUCCUUUUAGAGUAUCCUUAAUCUUUUUUGAUACUCAUAAUCUCAAUAGGAUUAAGUUACUUUAUGUCAUACAUCCUAUAUCCAAUUGGUUGGAGAUAGGGUGUGGUAUAGGGUGUAUGACAAGGUAACCUAAUUCUAUUAUGAUAAAUAUGAAGGUAUCCACUUAUUAGUGUGCAAAUGAAGGGACUACACAGCCAAACUAUGACUAGUGGUGUACAUUGGUUUGAAAGGUCAUGGCAGAACAAAAGGGAGGCAGGAGCCCUGUAGAUAUCAUGAUCACAUAAAUCUCACUUUGUCAUGAUAUUUAGCCCUUUUUUUAAUGUUGCUGGAUUUUUAUUUUAUUUUAUACUUUGUUAAAGAUUUUCAUGUGUAUGUUCUUGAGAGAUAUUGGUCUCUUGUUUUCCCAUGCUCUCUGUCUUGCUUUGGUAAAAGGGUAAUACCAGUCCCAUAGGGUGAGUUGGAAAGUGUUUCCUUGCCUGUGUUUUCUGAAAGAAUUGGUGUAGCAUUGGUAUUACUUCUUCUUUAUAUAUUGGAUGGAGUUUACUAGGUGAAGGCAUCUAGCCUGGGCUGGUGGUGGGGGUGGUGCAGAAGUGUGGAUUUUAAGUAAUGUAUUUUCUUGUUAUAGAGCUAUUCAUAAUUUCCAUUUUUUCUUUAGUCAGUUUUGGUAGUUUUUGGUUUUUGAGGAAUUUGGCUAUUUUAUCUAAAUUGUCUAAUUUGUUGACACAGUUAGCCAUAGUAUUCUCAUAAUCCUUUCAUUUCAGUAGGCUUGAUAAUGAUGUCCCCCUUUCAUUCCUGAUUUUGGUAUUCUGUGUCAUCUCAUUUUUUUCUUAGUCUAUCUAAAGGUUUAUCAGAUUAGUUGAUUUGUUUUCCCCCAAAGAACUUUUGGGUUCUUCUCUUUUCUCUUGUUUUUCUAUUGCCAAUUUCAUUGAUUUUUCCCUCUUCCUUCUGUUUGCUUUAUGUCUAAUUAACUGUUCUUUGUUCUUUUUUUUAAAAUUUAUUUAUUUUUGAGAUGGAGACUUGCUCUGUCGCCAGGCUGGAGUGAAGUGGCGCGAUCUUGGCUCAUUGCAACCUCCGUCUCCCGGGUUCAAGCAAUUCUCCUGCCUCAGCCUCCCGAGUAGCUGGGACUACAGGCGUGUGCCGCCAUGCCCAGCUAAUUUUUGUAUUUUUAGUAGAGACAUCGUUUCACCAUAUUGGCAAGGCUGUUCUUGAACUCCUGACCUCAAGUGAUCCGCCCACCUCCGCCUCCCAAAGUGCUGGGAUUACAGGCAUGAGCCACCACGCCUGGCCCUUCAUCGAUUCUUAAAGUGAAAGUUUAGAUUAUUGAUAUGAAACUGUUCUCUAUUGAUAUAGAUGUAUAAAGCUCUGAAUUUCUCUCUAAGCACUGUUUAAGUUGCACCUCAUAUGUUUUGAUAUGUUGUAUUGUUGUUUUCAUUUAGUUCAAAAUAUUUUCAAACUUCCCUUGCGAUUUUUCUUUUGACCCACAGAUUAUUUAGAAGUAUGUUACUUCAUUUCUAAGAAUUGCAGAUUUUCAAAGUUUCUUUCUUAUUUAUUUUUAAUUUACUUGUUUUCAGAUAAUAUACUUUGAAUGAUUUCCAUCCUUUUAAAUUUCUUGAGACUUGUUUUAUGGCCUGGCAUAUGGCCUAUCCUGGAAUGUUUCACAUGCACCUGAAAAGAAUGUAUAUUCUGCUCUUUUUGGAUGGAGUAUUCAAAAAUGUCAGUUCAAGUUGGUUGAUAGCAUUGUUCAAGUCUGCUAUAGCCUUGCUGAUUUUAUUCCUAUUUGUUCAACUGGUUAUUAAGAGUGAGAUAUUGUAAUCUCUGGCUGUAAUUGUUAAACUUUUUUCUUUCAAUUCUGUCAGUUCUUGCUUCAUGUAUUUUGAAGCUUUGUUGUUAGGUAUAUAUACCUUUAUAUCUGUUAUGCCUUUCAGAUGAAUUGGCCCUUUAUUAUUUUAAAAUAUCCCUCUUUGUAUCUACUAUAUUUCUUGUUUUAAAAGUCCAUUGUGUCUAUAAUUACUACAGCCACUGCAGCUCUCUUAUGAUUACUGUUUGCAUGGCAUGUCUUUCUGUUUUUUUCCUUUUAACCUAUUUGUAUCUUUUAAUUUGAAGUGAGUCUCUGGAAGACAGUAUAGUGCUGGAUGUUGCUUUUUUUUUUUUUAUCAGAGAAGCUUUGAUUGGAGUUUUUAGGUGCAUUAAAAUUUACUACAAUUUUGUUAGGUUUGCAUUUUCCAUUUUGCUAUUUGGUUACUGUGUAUCUUUCGUUAUUGAAUUGCUCUUUUAUUGCCUUCUUCUGCAUUAAACAGAUAUUUAUGAGGGUACCAUUUUAGUUUUUUUAACCUUUUUUUUUUUAGCUAUUUUUCUAAGUGGUGUCUCUACUUAUCAUAGGUAUCUUAACUUACUACGGCCUACUUCACAUGAAUAUUGACUAACUUCUGGUACAAUAUAGCAACUUUGCCCCAGUUUAGCUUCAUUUCCUUGCCCCUCCUUUGUGCUAUUAUGUCUUAUAUAUGUAUGUGUGUAUAUAUAUAUAUAUGUAUAUGUAUAUAUGUAUAUAUUACAGUGUUAUAAUUAUUGCUUUAUACAAUAAAGCAAUAUGUCUUCUAAAGAAUUUAAUAGAAGAAAUGUAUAUUUAUAGUUCUUUAUAUUUACUGACGUAGUAAUCAUUUCUGCUGCUCUUUCUUUGUUCCCAUGGAUUCUAGUUGCCAGGUCUGUUGUCAUUUCCUUUCAUCUAUAUUCUACUUCCUUUAGUAUUCCAAGUAAGGCAAGUAUGCCAGCAACAAAUUCUCUCAGUCUUUGUGGAUUUUGGAAUAUAUUUCAAAUUUAUAUAUGAAGGACAGUAUGUGAUAUAUUUAGAGUUCUCGGUUGACUUUUUUCCUCCAGCAUUUUGAAUAUGUCAUUCCACUGCCUUAUGGUCACCACUAUUCAUGAUGAAAAGUCAACUGUUAAUCCUGUUGUUCUUUAUAUAUGAUGAAUUGUUUUUCUUAUACUGUUUUUAAGAUUUUCUCUUUGGCUUUCAACAGUCUGAGCAUGGUGUGUCUAGGUCUGAAUUUGUGUUUAUCCUACUUAGAGUCUGUUGAGCUUCUAGGAUUUCUAGAUUUAUCCUUUUAAUACAAUUUAGGCAGUUUUUUGGCCACUAUUUCUUCAAUUAUUUUUUUCUGUCCUCGUUUCCUCUUUCUGGGGCUUUCAUAUACAUUAAUAUGCUUACCAUUGUGUCACAGGUCUUUGAGGCACUGUGCAUUCUUCUUUAAUCAUUAUUGUUUUUCAUAUUGGAUAAUUUUAUUAAUCUAUGUGCAAGUUUCCUGAUCCUUCUGCCAUCUCAAUUCUGCUGUUUAGCCUAUCUAGGAAUUUUCAUUUCAGCUAUUGAACUUUCUGACUCUAGAAUUUUCAUUUGGCUCUUUUUAAAUUGAUGCAUAAUAGUUGUACAUAUUUUGGGGAUAGACAUAUUUUGAUACAUGCAUGCAAUGUGUAAUGAUCGACCAGGGCAACUGGGACAUCCAUCACCCCAAACAGUCACCCCUUCUUUAUAUUGGGAACCUGCCAAUUCCUCCAGCAAUUUUGAACUUUACAACAAAUUAUUGUUAACUAUAGUUACCCUACUAUACUAGAGUGGUUGGUUAAUGGAUACAAAAACAUCAUUUUAUAUAUAUGUAUGUAUAUAUUUUAAGACAGUAUAUCACUCUGUCUCCCAGGCUGGAGUACAGUGGUGCAGUCAUGGCAGCCUUGAACUCCUGGGCUCAAGUGAUCCUCCCCGCUCAGCCUCCCAAGUAGCUGGGACUACAGGUGUAUGCCACCAUGCCUGGCUAAUUUUUUUUUUUUAAUUAUAAGUAAGGGAUCUCACCAUGUUGCCCAGGCUGAUCUCGAACUCCUGGCCUCCCAAAGUGCUGAAAUUUUAAGCAUGAGCCACCAGACCUGGCCACAUUUGGCUCUUUAAUAGUUACUUGUUUAAAAAUAGCUACAAAGCAGCUAUUACAAAUGUGUUUUAAAAAUUAAGGUAAAAUGUUUAAAGAAUUAAAAGCAUGACUUUUUUUUUAACCAGAGAUUCAUCAUUGAUCAUGUAUUCUUUUUUUUUCCUUUACUCUAAAAAAAAAAAAUACAUGUGCAGAACAUGCAGAUUUGUUACCUAGGUAUAUGUGUGCCAUGGUGGUUUGCUGCACCUAUUGACCCAUCCUCUUAAGUUCCCUCCCCUCACCCCAAACCCCCAACAGGCCCUGGUGUGUGUUGUUCCCCUCUCUGUGUCCAUGUGUUCCCAAUGUUCAGCUCCCAAUGUUCUCACUCACUUAUGAGUGAGAACAUGCAGUGUUUUGUUUCCUGUUCCUGUGAUAGUUUGCUGAGGAUGAUGGCUUCUAGCUUCAUCCACAUCCCUUGCAAAGGACAUGAUCUCAUUCUUUUUUAUGGCUGCAUAGUAUUCCAUGGUGUGUAUGUACCACAUUUUCUUUAUCUAGUCUAUCAUUAAUGGGCAUUUGAGUUGGUUCCAUGUCUUUGCUAUUGUAAAUAGUGCUGCAGGAAACAUACGUGUGCAUGUGUAUUUAUAGCAGAUUGAUUCAUAAUCCUUUGACUAUAUACCCAGUAAUGGGAUUGCCUGGUCAGAUGGUAUUUCUGUUUCCAGAUCCUUGAGGAAUCGCCAUACUGUCUUCCACAAUGGUUGAACUAAUUUACAUUCCCACCAACAGUGGAAAAGCAUUCCUAUUUCUCCUCAACCUCGCCAGCAACUAUUGUUUCCUGACUUUUUAAUAAUCACGUGAGAUGAUUGGCGUGAGAUGGUAUCUCAUUGUGGUUUUGAUUUGCAUUUCUCUAAUGACCAGUGAUGUUGAGCUUUUUUCAUAUGUUUGUUGGUCACAUAAAUGUCUCCUUUUUAGAAGUGUCUGUUCAUGUCCUUUGCCCACUUUUUGUUGGGGUUGUUUGUUUCUUGUUGGGGUUGUUUAAGUUCCUUGUAAAUCUGGAUAUUAGACCUUUGUCAGAUGGGUAGAUUGCAAAAGUUUUCUCCCAUUCUGUAGGUUGCCUGUUCACUCUGAUGAUAGUUUAUUUUGCUGUGCAGAAGCUCUUUAGCUUAAUUAGAUCCCAUUUGUCAAUUCUGGUUUUUGUUGCAAUUGCUUUUGGCGUUUUUGUCAUAAAGUCUUUUCCUAUGCCUAUGUCCUAAAUGGUAUUGCCUAGGUUUUCUUCUAGGGUUUUUAUGGUUUUGGGUUUUACAUUUAAGUCUUUAAUCCAUCUUGAGUUAAUUUUUGUAUAAGGUGUAAGGAAGGGGUCCAGUUUCAGUUUUCUGCAUAUGGCUAGCCAGUUCUCCCAGCACCAUUUACUGAAUAGGAGAUCCUUUCCCCAUUGCUCGUUUUCGUCAGGAAAAACGUGACUAUUUUAAAAUAGCAACUAUAAUACAAUAUUCCCUGUUGAGUCAUUGUCAUCAUAUUUUCAUCUUAUUUUUUUCUUUUCCAUAUAUUUUUCUGGUAAAUAUUUUUUGUCUGGUAAGAACACAGGAAGGUAAGAUAUACUCAACAAAUUUUUAAGUGCACAAUACAGUGUUGUUAACUAUACAUACAGUGUUUUACAUCAGAUCUCUAGAACGUUUUCAUCUUGAGUAACUAAAACAUUAUACCUGUUGAACAGUAACUCCCCAUUUCCCCUGACAGCCCCCUUCUAUUCUGUUUCUGUGAGUUUGACUAUUUUAGAAAUCUCAUGUAAGUGAAAUCAUGCAGUAUUUGUCCUUUUGUGACUUUUAGUCUUUAUUCAACAUCCAAGCACAUGCAUAGUUUUUCUUGACAGCUUUUUUCUUUGAUAUAAAUCAGACUUUCUGUUUCUUUACAUACGCUAUAAAUUUGUUGAAAACUGGAAAUUUUACGUAACAUAUUGUGGCAACUCUGGAUUUGGUAUUUGUUCCCCUGGGGGUUGUUAUUGCUGGUUUAUUAUUAUUGUUGUGUUGUUUCAUUAUUUGCUUAGACUUUAUCUGCAAAAUCCUCUAUGGUGUGUGCCUGCUGAUUUCUCCACUGUUGUUUUAAUUUGCAUUUCUAGUUUUUAGCUGGUCAUUUUAGGGGAUUUCUAUGCAUCUGUAUUGCUUAAUGAUUAUUCAAUUAUUGGUUGAAGGCUGUAUUGAAAAACCUUGAGUCAGUAGGUCUUCAUCCUAUGCUGAUGUGUCUGUGCAUUCAAUGUUCAGGCAAUUUUCCAGUCUUCCUCCACUUUGCUUCCCUCUGAGCGCUUCCAGGUCUUCCUGCUCAUGUGCACAUCCUCAUUAGUUCAGGGAUAUGUGGUGAGCAUGGGCUUUCUUAGGUUUUCCCUACAUAUGCACACAGCCUCCCACUCCAGCAGAGAUAUGCGGAGAGCUUAUUUAGCCCCUCAUUUCUAGACUUUCUUCCUGUUAAUUUAAAAAUUAGUCUGCCCAUCUCUUGCCCCAAAUGGGACUGCAAUCUCAGACUAGCGGAGCUAUGCAUCUUCCCUGUUUUUGUCCCUCUAACUUUACUGUUUUUAACUAACCCUACUACUGGGCAUGGGCUCCUUUCCUUCUACUCCAAAUCAAGUGAGCCCACUGUAGCAGAGAGGCUGCUAAUGUUCACUGUCAUUCCUACACUGUUAGCACUACCUCACUGAUCAAGCUGGGGAGCGGAAUGGGAGCAGCCCCUGGUAAGAACGCCUCAGAGUCUCACUGAUCUUCCAAAGUUCAGCAGCUUCUCAAUUUUGGUUGUUUCCCUUUGGUUGAUUUUUGGAGCCCUGAAAUGGUUGUUUUUCUUCUUUUUUCAGUUUUGUAGUAAUUUUUUUUGGGGGGGGCCGGUGGGGAGCUUCUUCACUCCAGUAUCACCAGAAAUUUCCUUAUUUUUAUUUAUUUGUUACGUACUGGAGUAAUCUCUUUUCUGUGUAUUUAUUAAUUUUUUCUUUAUUUUCCCCAACUUUUUAUAUUGAAAAUCUUCAUAAUCUGUAGAAAAUAAACACCUAUAUACCCUGCAUUUAGAUUUACCAAUUGUUUACUUUCUACAUUUGUUUUAUAUUUGUCUGUAAAUAUACAUAUGUAUGCAUGUACAUAGUAUGUACAUGUAUAUAAAAACAUUUUUCCUUAACCAUGAAGAUUAUUUGCAGACACCCUGAGUAUUCCUUCCUAAAUACUUCAGCAUACAUUUUCUAAGAACAAAAACAUUUUAUUUCUUAAAUACAAUUGUCAUAUUUAGGACAUUGAAUAUUGAUAAA